GAGAUCACACCACUGACUCCAGCCUGGGCGACAGAGGGAGACUCUGUCUAAAAAGAAAGUGAAGGGACUGUGUGAGUCCAGAGGAAAAGGGAAUAACCCCCUAGCCUGGGAAGGUGGAGAGGGCUUCCUGGAGGUGGUGAUAUUCCAGAUGAGUCUUGAAGGGGAAAGCCAAUUUUAGUUGUUGUAAAAAUGUAGAACUGUUUUUAAAAAAAAGUAGAAGUGUUACUUUUAUGGUCUGUCAACAAGGCUGUCCUGCCGCUUCUCCCAGACAUUGGCACCAUGCCUGCCCACCAUGCUAUGGCUGGAUAGGGAGAGUCCUUGCUCAGCUCUUCCCGCCCCUAUGCCUUGGCUUAUGGAUUUCUGUUUGCUUUCAUCAUUUUCUCCUUCAACUUGAGAACUCCUAUUCAACCUCUGAAACCCAGCUCAAAUGCCACCUCCUCUGUUCCAGGGCCUGCAGCUGGAGCGUGAGGCCUGCCUGGCCUCCAACUACGCGCUGGCCAAGGAGAACCUGGCCCUGCGGCCCCGCCUGGAGAUGGGCCGGGCUGCCCUGGCCAUCAAAUACCAGGAGCUUCGUGAGGUGGCCGAGAACUGCGCGGACAAGCUGCAGCGACUGGAGGAAAGCAUGCAUCGCUGGAGUCCCCACUGCGCGCUGGGCUGGCUGCAGGCUGAGCUAGAAGAGGCGGAGCAGGAGGCAGAGGAGCAGAUGGAGCAGCUGCUGCUCGGGGAGCAAAGCCUGGAGGCCUUCCUGCCUGCCUUCCAGCGUGGCCGCGCCCUGGCCCACCUGAGGCGGACGCAGGCAGAGAAGCUGCAGGAGCUGCUGCGGCGUCGGGAGCGUUCUGCCCAGCCGGCCCCCACCUCGGCUGCUGAUCCCCCCAAAUCCUUCCCGGCUGCAGCUGUCCUGCCCACUGGGGCCGCCCGGGGGCCACCAGCAGUGCCCCGGAGCCUGCCCCCCUUGGACUCCCGCCCAGUGCCCCCACUGAAGGGCUCCCCCGGGUGCCCCCUCGGCCCGGCCCCCCUGCUGAGCCCUCGGCCCUCGCAGCCAGAGCCCCCCCACCGGUAGGAUCCACGGUGCGGCCCCCCAGUUGGGGGGCCUAGACAAACUUGAUGCGUGGCUCCUCCUCCUCCCCCACUGCCUGGGUGGGGGGAGGGGCAGGCCCCUCCCCCUGGCCUCAGGCAGGCCCUGGCCCUGGAGGCUGAGCUGGGGAGGAGGGUCCCCUGGAAGAGGCCCGAGAGGGGGCUGGGGGUGGGUGGGCAGGGCUUUAUGCCUCUGGCGCUGAAGACACCCUGCCUUUUUUGUUUCCGUGCCCCGGGGCCUCUAGGGUGAUGGACCAGCCCCGUUAAAGAACUUGACUCAACUACAGGGGCCUGGGAAGAUGCCUGGGUCCCCUAGGGGCCUUGCCAAGGGGACCUGUCGCACCCCACCACUCCACUGGGCUCGCACAACGCCAAGGCCGCCAGGAGUGUUUUACAUCAUGUCCUGAGCCUACCUUUCCCCCAAAUUCUGGGGCCCACAGCCUAGGAGCCAGGUGAUCAGGCCUCGGCUGUGGGGCCAGGGACACCAUGGCCCUGGGGCUACUACGUGUCCACACAUGCUCCAGACCCUGGGGCAAGGUAGGCCAGGGGCUUCUGACCUGUGCAGGUGAGAGUGGGCCAUACCCAGGAAAGACCAUUCUGUAUUUUUCUGUCCCUGUCUCCUUAGAAUGGAAGCUUUUUGAGGGCAGGUCCUUGUCUUUGUACGUUCUGUCCCCAGCCCCGCCUCUUAGGGGCCGUCAAUAAAUGUGAUGAUGAGGAUGA